AGAGCCGCGGUCACGCGCCCGCCCGAAGGCUCCUGUCGGGACAGGGCGCCGCCCCGUGUCGGCCCCCGCAGAGCUCGCGGCCCCCGCCUGUCCGGGCGCCGCCAUGGAGCGCAUCGAGGGGGCGUCCGUGGGCCGCUGCGCCGCCUCACCCUACCUGCGGCCGCUCACGCUGCAUUACCGCCAGAAUGGUGCCCAGAAGUCCUGGGACUUCAUGAAGACGCAUGACAGCGUGACCGUUCUCUUAUUCAACUCUUCUCGGAGGAGCCUGGUGUUGGUGAAGCAGUUCCGGCCAGCUGUGUAUGCGGGUGAGGUGGAGCGCCGCUUCCCAGGGUCCCUAGCAGCUGUAGACCAGGACGGGCCUCGGGAGCUACAGCCAGCCCUGCCCGGCUCAGCGGGGGUGACAGUUGAGCUGUGUGCCGGCCUCGUGGACCAGCCUGGGCUCUCGCUGGAGGAAGUGGCUUGCAAGGAGGCUUGGGAGGAGUGUGGCUACCACUUGGCCCCCUCUGAUCUGCGCCGGGUCGCCACAUACUGGGACGCUACGAUGGGCUCCUGACCCCAGCUGAGGUCUUGGGGAAGGAGGAGGGUGUCACAGACCCCCACCCCCACCAGCUGAGCACCAGCCUCCACAGCCUCCUCCAGAGGCCAGGGCCCGCUCCACUGGGAGAAGCACCGGAAGUCUCUGCACCUGUCAGCCUGGCACAUGGGCCACUCAGGGUUGAGCCUGGGGCCCUCCCACCUCAGCAGCCUCAAGGACUUCACCUGGGCACGUUCCUGGCUGGAUGGGUGGACUCCCAAGUUAAAGGCAGCAUUUCCACGCUGGGCCAGGCACGGUGGCUCACGCCUGUAAUCCCAGCACUUUGGGAGGCCGAGGCAGGCGGAUCACCUGAGGUCAGGAGUUCGAGACCAGCCUGACCACAUGGAGAAACCCCGCCUCUGCUAAAAGUACAAAAUUAGCCAGGCGUGGUGGCAGGAGCCUGUAAUUCCAGCUACUCAGGAGACUGAGGCAGGAGAAUCGCUUGAACCCAGGAGGC